AGAACCCGCCUUGCGGUAGCCAUGGCAGCAGGCUCCGAGGCGACCACUCCUGUGAUCGUUGCGGCUGGGGCUGGAGGGGAGGAAGGUAGGUGCCAGGCUGAGGUCCGACCCUGAGUACAAACCCAAUGCCAGUUGACUCUCGUGGCACCCCUCGUGGGGCCGUUUGCCUUAGCCCCAACCCAGGUCUCUCUGGCCUUGCAUUAGACUAUGAAGAAAAAUCUAUAUUUUCUAGUGAGCGUGGCAUUUCUCGAAUUGUGGCAUCCAGAUUUUUGAUCGUCGUAGGGUAGCCUACGAGUGCUGUUUCACGCAUGGGGUGUUAUUUUUGUUUUGUUUUGUUUUAUAUUUGCCCAUCAUUAGCUAAAUAGAGGUGUUUUGAACGUUUAGAGGGGAUUAAAAUUAAAUUUGUGAAAUUGAAGGCAACCUUUGAGAUUAAUGGAAGUUAUCUGAGACUUUUGUGAACAGGGAUUAUGCGCUUUUAUUCUAUUUCAGUGAACCCUGGUUUAGCAAGUGGGGAUGAGGUUUGGAGGCCCAUGAGCCUGAGAUCCCUGUUAUUAUUUAUUGAAUGAUUGCACCGUGCAGGGCUGUGUUCUGAAUACUGUCGCAGGAUCCAGAGACUUUUGAAUAUUUAUAACAAUACCUUUUCCAAAGGAGCCUAGAAAGGAAAAAGAAUGACUUACUAUGUGGUCACCUGAACUAUUCUACCAGUAGUACACUCUGUGAGGGUUGUUAGGAGGAGGGAUCUCAGUGGGGAGAACAUAAAUGCUUCAAGGAGCGAAUAGUUUGAGGUCGGCCUUUCUUUUUCUUUUCUCUCUUUUUUUUUUUUUCUUUUUUUGAGACGGAGUCUCGCUCUGUCACCAGGCUGGAGUGCAGUGGCGCGAUUUUGGCUCACUGCAACCUCCACCUCCCAGGUUCAAGCAAUUCUUCUGCCUCAGCGUCCCAAGCAGCUGGGACUACAAGCGUGCCACCACGCCCAGCUAAUUUUUGUAUUUUUAGUAGAGACGGGGUUUCACCAUGUUGGCCAGGAUGGUCUCGCUCUCUUGACCUUGUGAUCCGCUGAGGUGGGCCUUUCUGAUUGGAUGAGAUGGUGACAAACUCAGGGAGUGGUGCUGGGGUUCAGGAAGUCAGGGAGCAGAAAAGGAUGGAUGUAUUUAGGGGUCAAACAGUUUGCUGAAGGGGGAGAUGCCCAUUCCAAGCAGAAGAAACAAAUUAUAGCCUCCUACUAUCUGACCACUUUCUACCAGGGAGACAAUUCUUGACCUUCAUCUAUACCUCCAUUGCAUUGAUCUUUCCAUUUUCUAUCCACUGCACCCCCUUAUCCAGAAUGUAUGUCGUUCCUUUGAAAAAUUCUCUUGUCCCUUCCUGCACUUUUUUCUGACAAAACUCUUACUCUGGAUGAAGUCAACCUUUUGCCCUCUUUGUACCUGCACCCGUGGGCCUGAACUUUGCUGGAAAAAGUCCUGCACAAACUGAUGACCGUAUAAAGUGAAAAUGGCCAAACUCUUGAAUAUUCAGUCAGUAUGGGCUUGAGAUCCCUCUGAUCCUCUGUUUCUCUAGUGAGCCUGCUAACGUUCUCCAAUGACAAAUUCCCAAACUCUAUAACCUCUCUCUGCCUCUUUCUUAAUUUCAGGUAAUGACUUUGCAAGUCAGGUCAAUUCUGCAUCUAAUCUGUCUACUUUUUUCCUUUCACUAUCAGACCGUACUUCAAAUCAUCCACAUUUUCUCACCUCAACUACUACUGUAUCUUCCUGACUGACUUGUGUCUCUGUUUUCUAUUCUGUGCCCCUCUAAUCCCUUCUCCACUCUGCAGCAAAAAGUGACUCUUCCUUAUGUAAAAUUCUUCAGCGAAUUACAUUGCCCUUAGAAGUUAGAAUAAAACCCAGAUUCUUAACCGUGGCCUGUAAUAAUCCUUGGUCUGGGCUCUGCUGAUGUCUUUAGCAGGAUCUCUUGUCACUCACCUCCCCUUUGGCUUUUCACAUAGCUGGCUUAAUCUUUAGCUUUUAAAGUAUGUCACCACCUGAGACCUUACCAGAUCAAACUAUUUAAAACAGUCACUGUGAUUUCUCUUGCACCCCCCAACCCUAGAUGUUCUGGAAUACAGCAUCCUGCUUCUGUCAUUUUACUUACUACAAUCUGUAAUUAUUUAUUAUUUGUUUUUUCCAUUAGAUCAUAAGUACCUUGAGGGCAGGACCUAUGUCUGUUUCAUUCUCUACCAUGUGCCCAGCUGCUAGUACAAUGCCAGGCACAUAGUUGGCACAUGCCACAUGUUUGUUGAGUGGAUGAAUAAGGGCACUCCAUGCCAAGUCCAGAGGCAAAAGGAGAAAGCAUGGCAUGGUCCAAGAACUGAAAGAAGUUGGUGUCAGGAGUGGUAAGAAAAGAGGUAUCCUGAAGGUUACCUUAGGCCUAGUUAAGGAAUCUAGACAUUAAGACAGUAGGAAGCCUUAAAGAGCUUUAGGUGAGGGAAAUAACAUGAUUAGAUUUGGUUGUAGGAAGAUCACUUUGGCUGAAGGGUAGAAGACCGAUUGGAGGGAGAAAGACUGGAGGACAAGGUACUUAAUCCCUUUGAGCCUCAGUUUCCUCCUCUGUAAAAUGCAUGAUUAUUGUGAAGAUUAGAGUUAAUAUGUGUAGAUUAUCUAGCAUAGUAUCUGGCAGGAAUUGGAUAUUCAAGAAUCGUGACCAUUUUUAUUAUUAAUAGAAAGUGCCAGCCUUAGUAACUGAUGUUGAAACUGAAAGAAAAGAAAUUAGAGAUGUUAUGUAAGAGAAUGAGAAAAAUAAAUACAUUAAAUAAAGUCAAGUGAAAGGGUCAGUAUGUUCAGUACAAUGAUGAAUACAAUGGGAGUCAUAGAAAAGUUCAUUUUUAAAAUUUUUGGUUUAUUUUUUAUUUUUGUAGAUACAGGGUCUCACAAUGUUCCGUAGGCUGGUCUCGAACUCCUGGCCUCAAGUGAUGCUCCCACCUCAGCCUCCCAGAGCACUGGGAUUUCAGGCAUAAGCCACUGUGCCCAGCUGAAAAGUUCAUUUUUGAGCAAACUUAUUCCAUUAUCAAAAAAUAUUUGAAUGGCACAUGGUAAACAGACCUUUUUCAUGUGGUAAAGCAAAAGACAAUCUUUGCCCCAAAAUAAUUAUAAAUAUCAUUUUUGGCAAUAAAGACAUAGAUAAAAAGAACAGUAGUAUAAGACAUAUCCUAAAGGUCAGAUGUAAUUAGCUGGGAUAUGAUACUCAAUAUGAUACACAUUAAGUACUUUGGAGGCUGAGAGGAGAAGGAACUAAUAGAAAUUGGGUUGGUUUGUGCUUCCUAGGAUAAUUUCUUGAAGAUGAGCCAGGUGAGGAUACCAAUUCUACUAAAGUAGAAAUAAUGACAGAGAACCUGGGUGAAAAAGGGGAAGACUUGUAUCCAUUGAAUCCAGAGAAGAGCAGGGUGAAAACAGAAAUGCUGAAGUGACGAAGAGGGAAAUCAUGGGUUUCAGUCUUUGCAGAAAAAUAGAGCAAGGUACCACAAAAGUAAGGAAGUAGAGAAAGGUACUGGAGAUUUGAGAGUGAAGAAGCAUCCAGGCAUGCUGGUGCAUGCCUGUAAUCCCAGCACUUUGGGAGGCGAGGCAGGCAGAUCGCUUGAGCUCAGGAAUUUGAGACCAGCCUGGGCAACAUAGUGAAACCCUGUCUCUACGGAAAAUACGAAAAUAAACUGGGCAUGGUGGCACACGCUUGUAGUUCCAGCUGCUUGGGAGGCUGAGGCACAAGAAUCGUUUGAACCUGUGAAGCGGAGGUUGUAGUGAGUUGAGAUCGUGCUAUGGCACUCCAGCCUGAGCAACAGGGCCAGACCCUGUCUCAAAAAAAAAAAAAAAAGAAGCUUUGGCAUGAUUGCCAUAGGGUUGCGGGUGAUUAGGAGUGAUAGGAGUGAGUCAGUGCUUGGGAGCAGGAAAGGGUAACUGGUAGAGGUGAGCAUAAAAUCGUGGAACUAAUCACCUUGGUUAUGCUUGAUAGCUCAUUCUACAGAAGUGGAGAAAACAAGUGCUUAGUUUCAAUAAAGUUUUAUACAUUGCUAAAAAUCAGGUAUUCUUAUACAGUUAUUUGAAAGAAACAUUUGUUUAGCAUCAUUUUAUGCUAGGCACUGGACUAACCUCUAGGGAGAUAAAAGUAAGAGGUCUGCCUUCAAGAAUGUGAUAUUGUUUGUUUGAAAUAACAGCUUAGAAAUAAUUAAAAACAAACAUGAAACUACUUAUUGUUAAUUAAGAAUUAAUUUAAAUUCUGAAUGUGAAAUGUUACUCUCAGAAUCAUACAUAGAUUGAAGCAUUCAGUGAAAUUAAAAAUUGCAGUUAUUUGAGUGUGAUUCUAUCUUUCAAACUGAGGUUAUUAUAUUUCUCUCUAUUGGGCUGUUUUUUAGUUUUUAGUUAUAGCCAAGAUUAUUCCUUGAUAAAGAGGAGAAUGUGUUAGUAACUCUUCUUCCAGUGCUUUCUGAGGAAAUAUCUCAUCUAGAGUUGUAUGGAAUUGAUUUUCACUUAGAACUAACAUUCCUACAUAACUGGAUUUAUCUUUUUCAGUUGGAGACCCGUACUCACCAUGUCAUUUUUGUUCUCAUUUUUAAAAGGGGCAAAGGGUGGAGGAGUUUAAAGAAAAGCAAAAGUCUGUGUUAUCUCAAAAAGUAAAAAAUUCCCAUGUUAGAAUCCAUAUGUAAUUCAUAAUGUAGAUAAAAUUUUUAAUUUCACUGAAUGCUUGGUAUUGAUGAGUAUCAGAAAAACAAUACCAUUUGUUUUAUUGUGGUAAAAACAUAUAACAUAAAAUUUACCAUGUUAACCAUUUUUCAGUGUUAGUAGUGUUAGGUAGGUACACAACAUUGUGAAGGUGAUCUCUAGAGCUUUUUCAUAUUGCAAAUCUGGAACUCUGUAUCCGUUAAACAAUAACUUCCCUUUCUCCUCUUCCCCCAGUCCCUGGUAACUGCCAUUUUAUUUUCAGUUUCUAGAAAUUUAACCACUUUAGAUACUCCAUAUAAGUGGAAUCAUAUAGUGUUUAUCUUCUUGUGACUGGCUUAUUUCAGUUAGCAUACUGUCUUCAAGGUUCAUCCAUGUUGUAGUAUAUGAUAGAAUUUCCUUCCUUUUUAAGGCGGAAUAACGUUCCAUUGCACGUGUAAGCAUUUUGCUUAUCCAUUCGUCAACAGACCUUUGAGUUGCUUCCACCACUUAGCUAUUGUAAUAGUGCUGCUGUGAACAUGGGUGUGCAGAUGUCUUUUCAAGACCUUACUGUAGAAUACUUUUGAGGAAAAGUAAGAUAAAAUAAUCAUUUAUUUUAAAUUAUCGAAAAUUCACUUGGGGAGGCUGGGGUUCAAUGGAAACAUUUGGGUAGAAAUUUUGGAGGUACGUUGCAAAAACCUUUAGUAUUUGAGACAUCAUUCCUUCUAGUGUUAACUUCACUUAAAAUAUAGACAGAUUUCCUUUUUCUUGCUUUGGUUUGAGACUAGUAUUACUUUUGAAUUUAUGAGCCAUUUUUUGAGGUAAAGAUAAGUUUUCUGGGUUAACUGAACAAGGGUUUAUAAGUGUAGGAGGAUGGAAAGAAGCUAAAAGGCUCAUGAACCUUUGGUAAGUGUCCAGGAUGUAACUGUCUCAGGUGCCCAGCCUGAACUUCCUGUGUGUUUACUGCCACACCAAGCAUUGGUAUUGAUAAGGCUAGGUCAUAACAGCCGCAGCACUAAUGUUUGUGGGUUUUUUUCAGUGAUAGACAUCACCUUCUAGACCUUGAAAUUCAAAGGGUUUAUGGUUAGCCGUCAUUGUACUUAAGUAUUAUGUUACCUUUCAGGAGAAUUUUCUUAGUUUGUGUUGACAUUUUAAAAUAGUGGUUACAAAAUGAAAAAUUCUUUUUGGUGUAAGUUUUACCAUUCAGUCUUCAGUACUAAUCCAGUAAUUUUGUCAGAUAGUACUUGCACGAUUCCAUCAGGUUUUUCUAACAUGACCCAAAUGGUCAUUAUUUUUUGCCCUAAUAUCUACCAUUCCAGAGGUUUUAAACUUUCUUAUAUGUAUAUACAAUAGUUGUUUGAUGAAACACCAUAUAUACACUUAGAUGUAUACAUUCAGAAAUAAAUGAUCUCACUGUGCCAGGACCCAGUUUUAAAUUCAUGCUGUAUCAUUAUAGUGAUUCUCUGUAGUGUAAUGUGUGACUUACUCUUAUGUCAACUUCUAAAGGUUUUUAAAAAUCUUUAAUUUUUUCAUUAAAAUUAUAUCUGAUGAGAGACAAGUUAAUUUCAAUUUCAAGAUUUUUGUUAUAUUCUGUUAAUAUUCGGAGUGUCCUGGACACAUGGUAAAUGUUCCUUAUUCUUGUCUUAAAGUCUAAAUCUCAGAUACAAAUCCAGGCCAGGUGUUAAUUGACAGACACCAGAUAGUUGGCGUUCUCAGAGAAAUUAGGUUUCAAAUUAUCUUGUACUUUACAUUAAUUUUAAAAAAUUACUGAGAAGGACGCAAUUUAUUUUUGAUGAUGUUUCACUAUCUCCAAAGAAUUAGUUGCAACUCAGGCUGUAAUAAAUUGACUGGAGAACAUCCUACAUUUGGAGAGAGAAAAAACUAUUGGGUAACACCCAGAUCACUAAUCUGUUUUUUUUCAGUAGUUUCUAAAUCAUCUAGUUAAAAAUUACUACCUGCUGCAAGUUUAGACCUAAAUACCCUUAUCCUUUGAAGACUGUUGAGGUUGCUUCAGAAUUUUUAUAGCUCUUUGCAAAAUAUUAUUAGCAUGGAAUAACUGGGUGCAUCCAUAGGCUGUUUAACUAAUACAGGGUAGCAUUGCAUUCUUCUUUAAAGGAAAUUGUAACAUUUAAAUUCAUUAAUUUAAUGGCCCAGUUUAUUGUUGAUUAAAUUAUCAGAAGCUAAAUUAGUUUUAUCUCACAACCAGCUGAUUGUUUUAUUUCACGAUGGGCCUGAAAUUCUGUAAAUAUGCUAAUUUCCUGUUAUGGUGAACAUCCUGCUACUCUGCUUUGCACACACUUCAUAGUGCUCUCAUUCAUUUAGCAAAUGUUUUGGCAUUUAAUAUAUACCAGUCACUAGGCCAGGCACUCUCUCAGCAAAUUUUAGUGUUGGAGGUCUCCUAUUAAAUAAUCUCUGGGAUGUGUGGGAUUUUUAGAUCAGAUAAUUACAUUUUUUAAAUUUAACUUUAUGCUAGAGAAGAAAUAUUUACUUCUUUAUAGCUUUUUUGUCAAAAUACUACUCAUGUGUUACUGUCGCCUGUGUCCAUAUUUAUAGAAGGCUACCCAGUUAUAUCUACCCAAGUAUGAACCAUUUUGGGAAUAAUCAAAGCCAUGUGAUCUAUUGGCUCUAAUGUAAGGUGAACAUGUCAAACCUUUUAAGCCAGAGAAAGCAAAAGAAAUUAUCAUGUCUUUACAACAACCUGCAAUCUUCUGUAACAUGGUGUUUGAUUGGCCAGCACGACACUGGAAUGCUAAAUACCUUUCGCAGGUCCUUCAUGGCAAGCAGAUACGAUUCAGAAUGGGGAUGAAAAGCAUGAGCACAGUUCCUCAGUUUGAAACUACAUGUAAUUACGUAGAAGCUACACUCGAAGAGUUUCUGACCUGGAACUGUGACCAGUCUAGUAUUUCUGGACCAUUUAGAGAUUAUGACCAUUCCAAGUUCUGGGCUUAUGCUGACUAUAAAUAUUUUGUCAGUCUAUUUGAAGACAAGACAGAUCUUUUCCAGGAUGUGAAAUGGUCUGACUUCGGGUUUCCUGGAAGAAAUGGACAGGAAAGUACAUUGUGGAUUGGCUCCUUGGGAGCCCACACACCCUGUCAUCUGGACUCCUAUGGUUGUAACUUGGUAUUCCAGGUACAAGGAAGGAAACGAUGGCAUCUCUUUCCUCCUGAAGAUACUCCUUUCCUUUAUCCAACUAGAAUCCCUUAUGAAGAAUCUAGUGUGUUCAGUAAAAUCAAUGUUGUCAAUCCUGAUUUAAAGCGUUUUCCUCAGUUCCGGAAAGCUCAAAGACAUGCGGUUACACUGAGCCCAGGACAGGUUCUCUUUGUUCCCAGACACUGGUGGCAUUACGUAGAAUCCAUUGAUCCUGUCACUGUCAGUAUAAACUCAUGGAUUGAACUGGAAGAGGAUCACCUAGCCCGGGUAGAAGAGGCAAUCACCCGUAUGCUUGUGUGUGCCCUGAAAACUGCAGAGAAUCCACAAAAUACCAGAGCCUGGUUAAACCCCACUGAGGUUGAGGAAACGUCCCAUGCAGUCAACUGUUGCUACUUAAAUGCAGCUGUUUCUGCAUUUUUUGAUCGCUGCAGAACAUCUGAGGUAGUAGAAAUCCAAGCACUGAGAACAGAUGGAGAGCACAUGAAAAAGGAAGAAUUAAAUGUGUGCAACCACAUGGAGGUGGGCCAAACAGGUAGCCAGAACUUGACCACAGGAACAGACAAACCGGAGGCAGCAAGUCCCUUUGGCCCUGAUCUGGUCCCUGUAGCACAGAGGUCCGAAGAACCGCCUUCAGAAAGAGGAGGCAUAUUUGGAAGUGAUGGGAAAGACUUUGUGGACAAGGAUGGAGAACACUUUGGAAAAUUGCAUUGUGCCAAGAGACAACAAAUAAUGAGCAACAGUGAAAAUGCAAUUGAGGAACAGAUUGCCUCAAAUACUACUACGACUCCUCAAACAUUCAUUUCUACGGAUGACUUGCUGGACUGCUUGGUGAAUCCACAAGUAACCAGGAUAGUGGCACAACUUUUGAUACAAGGAAGAAGUUUAUGAUUCAAGUGGAAGAUGACUUUUAAAAUAAUAUUUUUUAAAUAUAUAUUUUUAAGUAGUAUGACUAAAAUAAAGAUGAACCAGCAAAAGGUCAGUUUGCACAUUUGUAAAUGUAUUUAUCCUUACCGAAUUACAUGUCAGUCUGUUGCCACCUUCUUUCAUGCACAUUCCUCUUUGGCCAAACUGGCUGCUCUUUGUUUGUAAGCUUUUGUUCCUCUCUCAUCCCAUACUUUUAGCCUGUGUCAAAUGUAAGUCCCAAGUAUUUCCAGCAGGAAGUAAUGUCUUCCUCAGCCUCAACCAGGGACCAACCGGCUGCUUACUUUUGCAAAUAAAAUUUUACUAGAACACG